AGUCACGUGAGGCGCAGAUCCUGGCUGGGAGGGGGUUGGUAGAGGGGUCCAGAGUGGCAGUAAAGGAGGAAGAUGGCGGGGUGCAGGGGGUCUCUGUGCUGCUGCUGCAGGUGGUGCUGCUGCUGCGGUGAGCGUGAGACCCGCACCCCCGAGGAGCUGACCAUCCUUGGAGAAACACAGGAGGAGGAGGAUGAGAUUCUUCCAAGGAAAGACUAUGAGAGUUUGGAUUAUGAUCGCUGUAUCAAUGACCCUUACCUGGAAGUUUUGGAGACCAUGGAUAAUAAGAAAGGUCGAAGAUAUGAGGCGGUGAAGUGGAUGGUGGUGUUUGCCAUUGGAGUCUGCACUGGCCUGGUGGGUCUCUUUGUGGACUUUUUUGUGCGACUCUUCACCCAACUCAAGUUCGGAGUGGUACAGACAUCGGUGGAGGAGUGCAGCCAGAAAGGCUGCCUCGCUCUGUCUCUCCUUGAACUCCUGGGUUUUAACCUCACCUUUGUCUUCCUGGCAAGCCUCCUUGUUCUCAUUGAGCCGGUGGCAGCAGGUUCCGGGAUACCCGAGGUCAAAUGCUAUCUGAAUGGCGUAAAGGUGCCAGGAAUCGUCCGUCUCCGGACCCUGCUCUGCAAGGUCCUUGGAGUGCUGUUCAGUGUGGCUGGAGGGCUCUUCGUGGAGAAGGAAGGCCCCAUGAUCCACAGUGGUUCGGUGGUGGGAGCUGGCCUCCCUCAGUUUCAGAGCAUCUCCUUACGGAAGAUCCAGUUUAACUUCCCCUAUUUCCGAAGCGACAGAGACAAGAGAGACUUUGUAUCAGCAGGAGCGGCUGCUGGAGUUGCUGCAGCUUUCGGGGCGCCAAUCGGGGGUACCUUGUUCAGUCUAGAGGAGGGUUCGUCCUUCUGGAACCAAGGGCUCACGUGGAAAGUGCUCUUUUGUUCCAUGUCUGCCACCUUCACCCUCAACUUCUUCCGUUCUGGGAUUCAGUUUGGAAGCUGGGGUUCCUUCCAGCUCCCUGGAUUGCUGAACUUUGGCGAGUUUAAGUGCUCUGACUCUGAUAAAAAAUGUCAUCUCUGGACAGCUAUGGAUUUGGGUUUCUUCGUCGUGAUGGGGGUCAUUGGGGGCCUCCUGGGAGCCACAUUCAACUGUCUGAACAAGAGGCUUGCAAAGUACCGUAUGCGAAACGUGCACCCGAAACCUAAGCUCGUCAGAGUCUUAGAGAGCCUCCUUGUGUCUCUGGUAACCACCGUGGUGGUGUUUGUGGCCUCGAUGGUGUUAGGAGAAUGCCGACAGAUGUCCUCUUCGAGUCAAAUCGGUAAUGACUCAUUCCAGCUCCAGGUCACAGAAGAUGUGAAUUCAAGUAUCAAGACAUUUUUUUGUCCCAAUGAUACCUACAAUGACAUGGCCACACUCUUCUUCAACCCGCAGGAGUCUGCCAUCCUCCAGCUCUUCCACCAGGAUGGUACUUUCAGCCCCGUCACUCUGGCCUUGUUCUUCGUUCUCUAUUUCUUGCUUGCAUGUUGGACUUACGGCAUUUCUGUUCCAAGUGGCCUUUUUGUGCCUUCUCUGCUGUGUGGAGCUGCUUUUGGACGUUUAGUUGCCAAUGUCCUAAAAAGCUACAUUGGAUUGGGCCACAUCUAUUCGGGGACCUUUGCCCUGAUUGGUGCAGCGGCUUUCUUGGGCGGGGUGGUCCGCAUGACCAUCAGCCUCACGGUCAUCCUGAUCGAGUCCACCAAUGAGAUCACCUACGGGCUCCCCAUCAUGGUCACACUGAUGGUGGCCAAAUGGACAGGGGACUUUUUCAAUAAGGGCAUUUAUGAUAUCCACGUGGGCCUGCGAGGCGUGCCGCUUCUGGAAUGGGAGACAGAGGUGGAAAUGGACAAGCUGAGAGCCAGCGACAUCAUGGAGCCCAACCUGACCUACGUCUACCCGCACACCCGCAUCCAGUCUCUGGUGAGCAUCCUGCGCACCACGGUCCACCAUGCCUUCCCGGUGGUCACAGAGAACCGCGGUAACGAGAAGGAGUUCAUGAAGGGCAACCAGCUCAUCAGCAACAACAUCAAGUUCAAGAAAUCCAGCAUCCUCACCCGGGCUGGCGAGCAGCGCAAACGGAGCCAGUCCAUGAAGUCCUACCCAUCCAGCGAGCUACGGAACAUGUGUGAUGAGCACAUCGCCUCUGAGGAGCCAGCCGAGAAGGAGGACCUCCUGCAGCAGAUGCUGGAAAGGAGAUACACUCCCUACCCCAACCUAUACCCUGACCAGUCCCCAAGUGAAGACUGGACCAUGGAGGAGCGGUUCCGCCCUCUGACCUUCCACGGCCUGAUCCUUCGGUCGCAGCUUGUCACCCUGCUUGUCCGAGGAGUUUGUUACUCUGAAAGCCAGUCGAGCGCCAGCCAGCCGCGCCUCUCCUAUGCCGAGAUGGCCGAGGACUACCCGCGGUACCCCGACAUCCACGACCUGGACCUGACGCUGCUCAACCCGCGCAUGAUCGUGGAUGUCACCCCAUACAUGAACCCUUCGCCUUUCACCGUCUCGCCCAACACCCACGUCUCCCAAGUCUUCAACCUGUUCAGAACGAUGGGCCUGCGCCACCUGCCCGUGGUGAACGCUGUGGGAGAGAUCGUGGGGAUCAUCACACGGCACAACCUCACCUAUGAAUUUCUGCAGGCCCGGCUGAGGCAGCACUACCAGACCAUCUGACAGCCCAGCCCACCCUCUCCUGGUGCUGCCUGGGGAGGCAAAUCAUGCUCACUCCGGCGGGCACAGCUGGCUGGGGCUGUUCCGGGGCAUGGAAGAUUCCCAGUCACCCACUCACUCAGAAAGCCGGGAGUCAUCGGACACCUUGCUGGUCAGAGGUCCUGGGGGUGGUUUUGAACCAUCAGAGCUUGGACUUUUCUGACUUCCCCAGCAAGGAUCUUCCCACUUCCUGCUCCCUGUGUUCCCACCCUCCAGUGUUGGCACAGGCCCACCCCUGGCUCCACCAGAGCCAGAAGCAGAGGUAGAAUCAGGCGGGCCCCGGGCUGCACUCCGAGCAGUGUUCCUGGCCAUCUUUGCUACUUUCCUAGAGAACCCGGCUGUUGCCUUAAAUGUGUGAGAGGGACUUGGCCAAGGCAAAAGCUGGGGAGAUGCCAGUGACAACAUACAGUUCAUGACUAGGUUUAGGAAUUGGGCACUGAGAAAAUUCUCAAUAUUUCAGAGAGUCCUUCCCUUAUUUGGGACUCUUAACACGGUAUCCUCGCUAGUUGGUUUUAAGGGAAACACUCUGCUCCUGGGUGUGAGCAGAGGCUCUGGUCUUGCCCUGUGGUUUGACUCUCCUUAGAACCACCGCCCACCAGAAACAUAAAGGAUUAAAAUCACACUAAUAACCCCUGGAUGGUCAAUCUGAUAAUAGGAUCAGAUUUACGUCUACCCUAAUUCUUAACAUUGCAGCUUUCUCUCCAUCUGCAGAUUAUUCCCAGUCUCCCAGUAACACGUUUCUACCCAGAUCCUUUUUCAUUUCCUUAAGUUUUGAUCUCCGUCUUCCUGAUGAAGCAGGCAGAGCUCAGAGGAUCUUGGCAUCACCCACCAAAGUUAGCUGAAAGCAGGGCACUCCUGGAUAAAGCAGCUUCACUCAACUCUGGGGAAUGCUACCAUUUUUUUUCCAAAGUAGAAAGGAAGCACUUCUGAGCCAGUGACCACUGAAAGGUAUGUGCUAUGAUAAAGCAGAUGGCCUAUUUGAGGAAGAGGGUGUCUGCCCUUCACAAACACCUCUCUCUCCCCUGCACUAGCUGUCCCAAGCUUACAUACAGAGGCCCUUCAGGAGGGCCUCCUGUGCCGCAGGGAGGGUGCGUGGGGAAGAUGCUUCCUGCCAGCACGUGCCUGAAGGUUUCACAUGAAGCAUGGGAAGCGCACCCUGUCGUUCAGUGACGUCAUUCUUCUCCAGGCUGGCCCGCCCCCUCUGACUAGGCACCCAAAGUGAGCAUCUGGGCAUUGGGCAUUCAUGCUUAUCUUCCCCCACCUUCUACAUGGUAUUAGUCCCAGCAGGCAUCCCUGGGGCAGACGUGCUUUGGCUCAAGAUGGCCUUCAUUUACGUUUAGUUUUUUUUAAAACCGUGGAGGUUGCCCACGGGCCUCGGCACCUGGCCCUGGCAGCACAGCUCUCAGGCCCAGCCCUGGGCGACCUCCUUGGCCAAGUCUGCCUUUCACCCUGGGGUGAGCAUCAGUCCUGGCUCUGCUGGUCCAGAUCUUGCGCUCAGCACACUCUAGGGAAUAAUUCCACUCCAGAGAUGGGGCUGCUUCAAGGUCUUUUCUAGCUGAUUGUGGCCCCUCCAUUUUCCCCAUUUUCUUAUCUCCCUGACCAAAAUUGCUUUGACUUCUAAAUGUUUCUGCUUCCCAGAAUGCACCUGACUUAUGAAAUGGGGAUAAUACUCCCAGGAAAUAGCGCAGGACAUCACAAGGACCAAAAAGGCAAUUCUUAUUUAAAUGUUACUAUUUGGCCAGCUGCUGCUGUGUUUUAUGGCAGUGUUCAGAGCUUGAUCACGUUAUUUCUUCCUUUUAUUAAGAAGGAAGCCAAUUGUCCAAGUCAGGAGAAUGGUGUGAUCACCUGUCACAGACACUUUGUCCCCUCUCCCCGCCCCUUCCUGGAGCUGGCAGAGCUAACGCCCUGCAGGAGGACCCCGGCCUCUCGAGGGCUGGAUCAGCAGCCGCCUGCCCUGAGGCUGCCCCGGUGAAUGUUAUUGGAAUUCAUCCCUCGUGCACAUCCUGUUGUGUUUAAGUCACCAGAUAUUUUGUUCCCAUCAGUUUAGCCCAGAGAUAGACAGUAGAAUGCAAAUACCUCCCUCCCCUAAACUGACUGGACGGCUGCCAAGGAGGCCCCAAACCCAGGCCCCAUGCAAAGGCACGUGGUUUCCUUUUCUCCUCUCUCUGCAUCUGCGCUUUCCAGAUAAGCCCAAAGACAGCAACUUCUCCACUCAUGACAAAUCAACUGUGACCCUCGCUCCUUCCAUUUCUGUCCAUUAGAAACCAGCCUUUUCAGCAUCUCACCCAUUAGCAGCCCCAUCACCCAGUGAUCAGUCGCCUCAGUAAAGCAGAUCUGUGGAUGGGGAGCCUACGGGUGGUAAGAAGUGGUGUUUUGUGUUUCAUCUCCAGCUUGGUGUUCCAUGGCCCCUAGGCGAGGUGAUCAGGGAGUGGGGCCAAUGGGCCCCCGGCCCUGGCUUUGGGACCUUGUGCUGAGGGAUGAUUUGCUCCUGACCUUGAUUAACUUAACAGUUCCCAGCUGGAAGGGACACUUUCAGGACCCAGUCCACUGUAUGGCAUUUGUGAUGCAGAAUUAUGCACUGACAUGACCCUGGGUGACAGGAAAGCCUUUCGAGAGGCCCAAGGUGGCCUCGCCAGCCCUGCAGUAUUGAUGUGCAGUAUUGCACCACAGCUCUGCGGACCUUGGCCAUUGCCGCAGUCGCAGCUUCCUUUUUUCUGUUUGCACUGUUUGUUUGUAUGAUGUUAGCUAAUUCCACUGUGUAUAUAAAUUGUAUUUUUUUUAAUUUGUAAAAUGCUAUUUUUAUUUGAACCUUUGGAACUUGGGAGUUCUCAUUGUAACCCUAACAUGUGAGAAUAAAAUGUCUUCUGUCUC